CCCUAUGUCUUCCCCCAACCCUGAGGAUGUGCCCCGGAGGCCAGAACCUGAGCCCUCAAGCUCCAAUAAGAAAAAGAAGAAAAGAAAGUGGCUGCGGCAAGAAGCCAGCAUCCAAGCCCUCACCAGGGCUGGCCAUGGGGCCCUUCAGGCUGGCCAGAACCAUGAAGCCUUGAACAACUUCCAGAGGGCCUUCCUUCUGGCCUCCAAGGCCCCACAAACCAGGGAUACCCCUGUGCUCCAGGCCUGCGCCUUCAACCUGGGGGCUGCCUAUGUGGAGACUGGGGACCCAGCCAGAGGCCUUGAGCUACUCCUGCGAGCCCACCCUGAAGAGAAGGCACAGGGCAGGCGACACGGCGACCAAUGUUUCAAUGUGGCUUUGGCCUACCAUGCCCUCGGCGAGCUGCCUCAAGCUUUGGCCUGGUACCACAGGGCCCUGGGCCACUACCAGCCACAGGGUGACCAGGGAGAAGCCUGGGCAAAAAUGGGAGCCUGCUACCAGGCUCUGGGACAGCCUGAGCUAGCAGCCCACUGCCUGCAGGAAGCAAGCCAGGCCUAUGCUCAAGAGAGACAGCUGCGGGCCGCAGCCCUGGCACUGGGGGCUGCGGCAGGAUGUAUGCUGAAGAGUGGGCGGCAUCGGGUGGGGGAAGUUGUGCAGGUGCUGGAGAAAAGCCGGAGGCUUGCCGAGAGGAGCACUGAGAGGCGACUGCUGGGGCACCUCUAUAACGAUCUAGGCCUGGGCUACUCCCAGCUCCAGCUGUUCCCGCUGGCCGUGGAGGCCUUCCUGCAGGCCCUGCCCCUGUGCUGGGUGCCAGGAGAGCAGGCCACAGUGCUAAGAAACCUCGGGAUGGCCCACAAUGCCCUCGGCAACUAUCAGGAAGCUCGGGAGUUUCACCAGAAGGCUGCUGACCUACACGGCUCUGUGGGGCAGCGGUGGGAGCAGGGCCGGAGCUUUGGCAGCCUGGCCUUUGCAUUGAGCCAGCUGGGGGACCACAAGGCUGCCAGAGACAACUACCUGCAUGCCCUGCAGGCUGCCCGGGACUCUGACUUCGGCUCCGGGAAGACUCCAGGCUCCAGGUGGGGCCAGCCAGGCGGAGGGGACCCCAGCAAAGGCAGGAAGCAGCACAGCAGGUGUCCAGCACAGAUCUUCCAGUGGGUGGGAAGAUGAAGAGUUUGAGGAGGGCCACCAGAAGAAAAAAGAGGAGAGGUCGGCAAACGUUCCGGUGAGGGCUGGGCCGGGAAGACCAGAGCGUGAGUUGAUGUAGAGUAUUCCUGGCGGUGCCUCUCCUUACUGCAAAUAUGGCACUCCCACCCCCACCCGCCUGCCUCCGCUUCUUAUGCCCAUCCCACCAUCCCGCCUUCCUGUUGUCAUUUCUUUGAGGCCUGGCACAACCUCGCGCCACCCCUGACCCUGGCUGUCCCAGUUCGCAAGUCCCCAACAGCCCUCCCAUGAUUUCUGCUUGUCUCUCAAGGCCCUGGACCAUUUUCCCUGAACCCUUCUAGAACUCCCUCUUCCUUCCUGCUCUCAUGGCUUUCCUAACUUCUAGAACUUUGCAUCUUGGACCCCAGGGUUUUGCUGAAAGCCUACUCUGUGCCCAACACAGCGCUGGGUGCUGUUGGUAAACCCCAGCUCACUACUCAAUAGCAUCUCCCACAAAGACUUGCAACUCAGGGAGCAGAGUUCUUUGCUACUUGUUGAGCUGACCUGAAUUUACCGAUGUCUCCUUUUCAGUGUGUUUCCUUCCAGGCACAGUGAAUCAUUCGCACCAUCUAGCUUCUAGUUGCCCCACGUUUACCAAGCACACGCCCUGCAGAGGGACAGUCCUCGGCAAAGCCUCCAUCUAUAGUGAGCAGUGCAUCCCCUGACACCGCCCCAACUCGUGGUUCUUCUCUCAGAGCUUUUUUCCACCAUGAUAGUUCUUGGUGCAGAGAGGCACGUGAUGAAUGUGUCUGUCCUUCUCCAUCUAGGUCCAGGACCCAGGGCCCAUCUUCCAUUUGUAGGUCCAGGCCCUCCCAGAGCGGAGUACCCUAGCAUCUUGGUACCCAAUGGCCCUCAAGCCAAUAGGUGGGUCCUUGGGGGAAAGAAGGAGGCCUGGAGAAUAGCAAAAAAAGUAGAAUGUGUGGCUUGGGAUGAUUUUAAUGAAACACGACUGCUGUUGAAGUUGGGGGAAGCUGGGAUCUCAUGCUUGGGAUAUAGGGCCCCGAGCCCCACUUUGUCUUUGCCCUUUAGCAAUGUGAACAACCCUCACCCGGCUCUGGAAGCCCAGGGUAUGCCCUGCUUCCUAAAUGGCCUGAUGGUAGGCCUCAGUGAAAGACAGGGUGCUGCAGGAUGGGGGGAUAUGAAGCUUAAGCCAACUCCCUCCUUCUCUGGAGCCCACCAGCAGAGGUAAGGGCCAAAUAGGGCAGAGGGAAGCUGAGGCCAAGGCAGGCUGCCUCCUGCUGUCUCCCCAGUCACCCCCACUGGCAAGCCCCUCCCUGCCUCUUUCAGGUCAUCCAGGUGGCCCAGGGAAAGCCUCAGCAGGAGCCGCCAGAGGAGACCCAUGGAGUCGGGCAUCUGCACUAUUGUGUGACCUCCCCCUGCCAGCCUCAGCCCUCAUCCCUGAAGCACCUGUCCAACACGCACACACUAGGGGGUCCUGGGGACCAAGCCUCUUCCCAGUUGCUCAGCCCUGCAGGGAUGUGGAACACAGUGCAGCCAGUGGACUCCUGAGGAGGCUGGCCAAGGGCUUUGCAGGCUCGGCCCUGAGAGGUUCUGUUUGUUCCUCCUUGGGAUUUUUGGACUCAGUAGGUAAAAGAAAAAAGGAAAAUGGAUGGCAAAUUCCCUGUCUUUCUGAAUCCAAAUCUUACGAUUGCUAGGGGCCUGGCAGUUCUAAAAACUGACUUCGUGGUCAAGUAGCUUUGGAGUCACUGACUGUCUCCAGACGUCCAUUUUUGCACAUGAGAAAUGAGGAUAUAAUACUACAGAAGAGGCAUCUUACCCAACCAAUGCACCUUACUUCUCUGUGAAACACAGGGGAUGCUGGGCGCAGGCCUAGGCUGUGGCCUGUAGCCUGUAGGACAGCUCCUGCCAGCAGCCACAGGAACAGUGAUGUGAUGUAACAUUUCCCAAGUACUUAGCUCAUGCCCCACCCUAUUCUAGGUGCUUAGCUCAGGCCCCACCCUAUUCUAGGUGCUUAGCUCAGGCCCCACCCUAUUCUAGGUGCUUAGCUCAUGCCCCACCCUAUUCUAGGUGCUUAGCUCAUGCCCCACCCUAUUCUAGGUGCUUCACAAGUGUAUUCUCCUCUAAUCCUCACAACAAAUAUAUGAGGUGCUAUUAUCCCCUUUCGCAAAUGAGGAAAAUAAGGCACAAAGCUUCAGUAAUCUGAAUUCCCAGGUCACAUAACUAGUAUGUAGAGAAGCUGGGAAUCAAACCCAGGCAGUGAGCACUUUCUAGAAUGCUGUGCAGUUCCACUUCCCCAGCUAAGCCCUUGCUUACCCAGAGUCCAUUGUGAUUUAAUAUCAAGUGUGUCUAUGCCCGUUGUAUGUGUUAUUGUAAUUCAUAAUGUAAUUAAAUACUAUACACAUUGAUGAACAGGCCAGGUGAGAUGGCUCACCCUUGUAAUCCUAGCACUUUGCGAGGCCAAGGUGGGAGGAUUGCUUGAGCCCAGGAGUUUGAGACCACCCUGGGCAACAUAGUGAGACCCCAUGUCAAUGUAAAAGAAAAUUUAUCUUUAAAAAAAAAUAAAUUGAUGAACUGAGAGUGGGAAAAGCAGCACUGUUUCUAUAAAAACUAAGUUGGAUCCUUAGAAGACUCGACUAAGGUAAGUUACUUUUUCUUUAUUAUUCUUAUGCUUUAUCUUCCAGUG